GUAGUCUAACCCCCUCGGAUCCAACAGCAACCUCAGUGCGUGAACUCUGUUAUCCAGAAGGCCUCGCCCUGCCGCCGCCGAAGCUGGAAUUCGUCGGCUAGUAGUUCUCGCCGGCAACUAGAGGAACCUGUUGGCGUGGCCCAGAAGGCUUAGCGGGAUUGCACGAGCCCUCAGAUUCAUCGCUACCCCGAGGCUAAGCGCCAUGCCUCAUAUUGACAACGAUGUGAAACUGGACUUCAAGGAUGUCCUUUUGAGGCCCAAACGCAGUACCCUUAAGUCUCGAAGUGAGGUGGAUCUCACAAGAUCCUUUUCAUUUCGGAACUCAAAGCAGACAUACUCUGGGGUUCCCAUCAUUGCUGCCAAUAUGGAUACUGUGGGCACCUUUGAGAUGGCCAAGGUUCUCUGUAAGUCCUAGGUUCCUGGGAGUUUCUGGGAUGUGCCCCAAAUGGGAUGUGUUUUUCUUAUAUACAAGUUGUUCACUUUGAAAUGGAAGAUGCUGCUCCUGUCAGUACUAUUACCUGCCUCUAUACUUGUUGCUGAGAAGUUCUCUCUCUUCACUGCUGUCCAUAAGCACUAUAGCCUCGUUCAGUGGCAAGAGUUUGCUGGCCAGAAUCCUGACUGUCUUGAGCAUCUGGCUGCCAGCUCAGGCACAGGCUCUUCUGACUUUGAGCAGCUGGAACAGAUCCUGGAAGCUAUUCCCCAGGUGAAGUAUAUAUGCCUGGAUGUGGCAAAUGGCUACUCUGAACACUUUGUUGAAUUUGUAAAAGAUGUACGGAAGCGCUUCCCCCAGCACACCAUCAUGGCAGGGAAUGUGGUAACAGGAGAGAUGGUAGAAGAGCUCAUCCUUUCUGGGGCUGACAUCAUCAAAGUGGGAAUUGGGCCAGGCUCUGUGUGUACUACUCGGAAGAAAACUGGAGUGGGGUAUCCACAGCUCAGCGCAGUGAUGGAGUGUGCAGAUGCUGCUCAUGGCCUCAAAGGCCACAUCAUUUCAGAUGGAGGUUGCAGCUGUCCUGGGGAUGUGGCCAAGGCUUUUGGGGCAGGAGCUGACUUCGUGAUGCUGGGUGGCAUGCUGGCUGGGCACAGUGAGUCAGGUGGUGAGCUCAUCGAGAGGGAUGGCAAGAAGUACAAGCUCUUCUAUGGAAUGAGUUCUGAAAUGGCCAUGAAGAAGUAUGCUGGGGGCGUGGCUGAGUACAGGUAUGUGUGGAGGCCCAGGAGCUUAGUAAUAGUAUGGAGGCAGAACUCAUGGCUGCUGAGAGGGGGAUGGUACAGUUCUCAGAGAAGCAUGGUGAACCGGGGCUCAAUGCUAGGGUCUGUGGAAAAGUCCCUGGGCUUAAGGAAUCCAGAAGGAGAAGAUAAUAAAGUUUUUCCUACUUUAAGAGCCUCAGAGGGAAAGACAGUGGAAGUUCCUUUUAAAGGAGAUGUGGAACAUACCAUCCGAGACAUCCUAGGAGGGAUCCGCUCUACGUGUACCUAUGUGGGAGCAGCUAAGCUCAAAGAGUUGAGCAGGAGAACUACCUUCAUCCGAGUCACCCAGCAGGUGAAUCCAAUCUUCAGUGAGGCGUGCUAGACCUGAGCAGUUCUACCCUCCCAAGGCACCAGUACUCUACCAUGGGGCAUCCCAAGUGGGGUCCUCACCCAUCCCAGCUACUGCAGCUCUGUAUUACUUUGUCAUUUCCUGUUGUCUCACUCCUGAGGGCUCCUGCAGUAACUCUGUACUUCUCUAUCUGCACACACAAAAUGCCCAAGGCACUCACUGGGGAGGAAGCAAGGAAGCAAACAGUCUGAGAAAAUGAUGCAAGAAAAUCAAAUGGGAAUCUGGGGACCCAACACAACAUCCUGAAGAUUAUUAAAAGGAAAAGAUGCUGAUUGGUACAUAAAUCUUUUACAUGGCCUUGGUCUAGAGGAGGCAGGCUUUUAGAAUCAUGUUUUGUUAAUCCGCUUCACUAAAUUGGACCUUCACAUAUCUAAAAAGCUCUGAAGUGUUUGUAUAUUUGAAAUACCUCAAUAAAGAGAGAGCUCAUUGACUGUAAA